CUUCGCGCACCUCAUGGAAUCCCUUCUGCAGCACCUGGAUCGCUUUUCCGAGCUUCUGGCGGUCUCAAGCACUACCUACGUCAGCACCUGGGACCCCGCCACCGUGCGCCGGGCCUUGCAGUGGGCGCGCUACCUGCGCCACAUCCAUCGGCGCUUUGGUCGGCAUGGCCCCAUUCGCACGGCUCUGGAGCGGCGGCUGCACAACCAGUGGAGGCAAGAGGGCGGCUUUGGGCGGGGUCCAGUUCCGGGAUUAGCGAACUUCCAGGCCCUCGGUCACUGUGACGUCCUGCUCUCUCUGCGCCUGCUGGAGAACCGGGCCCUCGGGGAUGCAGCUCGUUACCACCUGGUGCAGCAACUCUUUCCCGGCCCGGGCGUCCGGGACGCCGAUGAGGAGACACUCCAAGAGAGCCUGGCCCGCCUUGCCCGCCGGCGGUCUGCGGUGCACAUGCUGCGCUUCAAUGGCUAUAGAGAGAACCCAAAUCUCCAGGAGGACUCUCUGAUGAAGACCCAGGCGGAGCUGCUGCUGGAGCGUCUGCAGGAGGUGGGGAAGGCCGAAGCGGAGCGUCCCGCCAGGUUUCUCAGCAGCCUGUGGGAGCGCUUGCCUCAGAACAACUUCCUGAAGGUGAUAGCGGUGGCGCUGUUGCAGCCGCCUUUGUCUCGUCGGCCCCAAGAAGAGUUGGAACCCGGCAUCCACAAAUCACCUGGAGAGGGGAGCCAAGUGCUAGUCCACUGGCUUCUGGGGAAUUCGGAAGUCUUUGCUGCCUUUUGUCGCGCCCUCCCAGCCGGGCUUUUGACUUUAGUGACUAGCCGCCACCCAGCGCUGUCUCCUGUCUAUCUGGGUCUGCUAACAGACUGGGGUCAACGUUUGCACUAUGACCUUCAGAAAGGCAUUUGGGUUGGAACUGAGUCCCAAGAUGUGCCCUGGGAGGAGUUGCACAAUAGGUUUCAAAGCCUCUGUCAGGCCCCUCCACCUCUGAAAGAUAAAGUUCUAACUGCCCUGGAGACCUGUAAAGCGCAGGAUGGAGAUUUUGAAGUACCUGGUCUUAGCAUCUGGACAGACCUCUUAUUAGCUCUUCGUAGUGGUGCAUUUAGGAAAAGACAAGUUUUGGGUCUCAGCGCAGGCCUCAGUUCUGUAUAGGCAAUGCUGUGUUAUUACUUGAAUAUAGAAUAUAUAGUUUACAAAAUGAAAAUUACAAUGUUCUCACCAAAUAUAUGCCUUCGUGUGUCCAAAGUAUAAUUAUUUUAGAUGCUAAUUUUGAAUAGUUUAUUAAACAGUUAUAAAUAUGCAAAGUAGCUGGCAUGUAGUGUCACGGAUUUUCUGGAUAGAGGAAGUGAUUGGAAGUACUCCACUUAAAGCCAUGGAAUUAGCAAUAGUUUGCUUUUUAAUAGAAGGCCCAUUUGUAAGAAUGUUGAAAAUAUGUGUACCGUUUAAAGAAAAAGCAGCUUUAAAGUGACAAACAAAAUACCCUUUUUCUUUUAGUAUGGUUUAUUUUUCUAGGUUUUCUGUCCCUCCCUCAGUAGUGAAGAGUUUUCUUUAUUCCUGGCAGUGUCAGGAAUAUUGGUUUGAAAAGCUGUUGGCCUAUCUGGAGUUUGGCCUUGUUAACCUAGUAUUCUAACCAGUUAACCAGCCUUAGUAUGCAUUAAAAUUGUAUUGUUCAGAAAGUUUGUUUCUCAUUUUCUGCAAAUUCUUACUUUGAAAAUGAAUCACCACAUAGUAUGUCCCUUUAAAGCAUUGACGCACAGACAAAUGUUUAAAGCACAGUAAAUACGAAUAUAUGCCUUUGGAUAUUAAAUUAAUGCUUGAUGAUAAAAGAAUCAAACUUUUUUUUUUUUGAGAUGGAGUCUCGCUCUGUCACCCAGACUGGAGUGCAGUGGUGUGAUCACUGCUCAGUGCAACCUCUGCCUCCCAGGAUCAAGCAAUUCUGACUCAGCCUCCCAAGUAGCUGGGAUUACAGGCGCAGGCCACCAUGCCCGGCUAAUUUUUUGUAUUUUUAGUAGAGACGGGGUUUCACCAUGCUGGCCAGGCUGGUCUCAAACACCUGACCUUGUGAUCCGUCCGCCUUGGCCUCCCAAAGUGCUGGGAUUACAGGCGUGAGCCACCGCGCCUGGCCAAAACAACAUUUUAAGUAGAAGAUCCAGGUUUUAGUGCAGCUUCUGCCGUUAACUAGGUUAAUAAAUCACAACCUUGGGGCCACAGUUGCCUUAUAUGUAAAUGAAGUGUUUAGAAUAAAAUAGUUAAAUUUCCUUAUUUUUCCCUUGGUGGCUGCCCUGUGGAAACAGUUUAGAAUAUUUGUUUUGUGUGUAGGAACCUAGUUGUGUUAGUUUACCUGGGUGUUCCACAGCUGAUAGUGAUUGCCUUGAAUAAAUUCAAGGGCAAUUUAUUCAUUUUUACUAGGGAGAUAGACCUUUACAGCAAUCAAGAUAUUUUUGUCCAUAUCCAGGUUAGCUGGUAAGAGGAUUUUUUUGGAGAAAAAAAUGAUAUUUAGAAAGUUAAUUUCUAAUUCCGGAAUGGAAUAAAAACAAUAUGAGUAGUGUAAUCUUGUAGAAAAAGAGUUGUAUAAUCUUGUAGAAUUUCUCAUUCUGUGGUACAACCCAGGGGUAAACUAUUAUUCCAGUAGUCAGUACACUUUUCUAGAUAAAUCUUGAGUGAAAACCAGCAAUUUCUUUUUCCUUGUGGUCUGAUUCCUUUUUCUAAUCCAUGAAGGCCAUCUUGUAGAUUACAUUUAUCAUUAAUGCAAGAAUAAAGACAAUUCCUCCUGUCAGUUGCGUGAAUUUUUUUUAAGAAACAACCCAGUGAAGAGUUCUACCAUAGCAAGGCCUAAUGUUAGCUUUAGCUUUAGAAAAUAACAGUUUGUGAACUUACUUCCCUAUAUUUGCAGCUGUAUCUCACACUAUGAUUUACAAUAAAAUUGUAAAGAUUGACAAUAGACUUAAGAAAUAACAUUUUAAAAUCUAUUUUAUACUUACCAUUUAUUAUUCUGUUAUUUUAGUCUCCAUAUGUUCAUUACAUACAUAAUCUUAUUUAAUCUUCACACCAAAACUGUAUUCUUAUGAAUAUACGCUAAAAGAUUAAGUAAAAUGCCCAAGGGUAUAAACAAAAGCAACAUGAAAGUGGAAGCCGUAUCUGUCAUUUAUUUUAUUUCCAGAAGCCUAGCACAGUGUCCAGCAUAUGGUAGAUACUUGUAGUGUUUGAAUAAAUGAAACCAGCAUUAGAGCUUUAUAUACUUUCUCUUAAGGACUUGAAAAGAUUAGGAAUCUACGCAUACACUGAGAGAGAAAAAAGUGAGAGGA